UUUUACUCUGUUAGAAACAAAAACAACCACAAUACAAGCCAUAAUGCAAAGAAUGGUUCAGGCAGUAAGUUGUUAAAGUACAAAUGAUAAAGACAUUACAUCGGGAUUUGAGGACCUGGAAAAGGAAUGAAGCUGCCUAGCUGCCCUUGUGAGUGUACUUGUGAGGGAGCAGAAGGUGGCUGGAGCUAGGGUGGGGCCUGCAAUGGGCACAGUCAGAGCAGAUAGAGCCUCUCCAAGUUCUAACGCAUAUGUGAAAAUCUAGUAAUUUCUAUAAUGAAGCACAACAGAAAUGUCUAUCAACAGAUUUUGAAGAUAAUCUGGAAGCCUUGUAGAUCCCCAUUUGACCUAUGGAAGCUGUUUCUUGAGAGUCAUUGAUUCUGAUUUCAGAGUAUGGUAGUUCCAAUUUGCCAGCAGAAUGAGUACAGAAAGAGACUCAGAAACGACAUUUGACGAGGAUUCUCAGCCUAAUGACGAAGUGGUUCCCUACAGUGAUGAUGAAACAGAAGAUGAACUUGAUGACCAGGGGUCUGCUGUUGAACCAGAACAAAACCGAGUCAACAGGGAAGCAGAGGAGAACCGGGAGCCAUUCAGAAAAGAAUGUACAUGGCAAGUCAAAGCAAACGAUCGCAAGUACCACGAACAACCUCACUUUAUGAACACAAAAUUCUUGUGUAUUAAGGAGAGUAAAUAUGCGAAUAAUGCAAUUAAAACAUACAAGUACAACGCAUUUACCUUUAUACCAAUGAAUCUGUUUGAGCAGUUUAAGAGAGCAGCCAAUUUAUAUUUCCUGGCUCUUCUUAUCUUACAGGCAGUUCCUCAAAUCUCUACCCUGGCUUGGUACACCACACUAGUGCCCCUGCUUGUGGUGCUGGGCGUCACUGCAAUCAAAGACCUGGUGGACGAUGUGGCUCGCCAUAAAAUGGAUAAGGAAAUCAACAAUAGGACGUGUGAAGUCAUUAAGGAUGGCAGGUUCAAAGUUGCUAAGUGGAAAGAAAUUCAAGUUGGAGACGUCAUUCGUCUGAAAAAAAAUGAUUUUGUUCCAGCUGACAUUCUCCUGCUGUCUAGCUCUGAGCCUAACAGCCUCUGCUAUGUGGAAACAGCAGAACUGGAUGGAGAAACCAAUUUAAAAUUUAAGAUGUCACUUGAAAUCACAGACCAGUACCUCCAAAGAGAAGAUACAUUGGCUACAUUUGAUGGUUUUAUUGAAUGUGAAGAACCCAAUAACAGACUAGAUAAGUUUACAGGAACACUAUUUUGGAGAAACACAAGUUUUCCUUUGGAUGCUGAUAAAAUUUUGUUACGUGGCUGUGUAAUUAGGAACACCGAUUUCUGCCACGGCUUAGUCAUUUUUGCAGGUGCUGACACUAAAAUAAUGAAGAAUAGUGGGAAAACCAGAUUUAAAAGAACUAAAAUUGAUUACUUGAUGAACUACAUGGUUUACACGAUCUUUGUUGUUCUUAUUCUGCUUUCUGCUGGUCUUGCCAUCGGCCAUGCUUAUUGGGAAGCACAGGUGGGCAAUUCCUCUUGGUACCUCUAUGAUGGAGAAGACGAUACACCCUCCUACCGUGGAUUCCUCAUUUUCUGGGGCUAUAUCAUUGUUCUCAACACCAUGGUACCCAUCUCUCUCUAUGUCAGCGUGGAAGUGAUUCGUCUUGGACAGAGUCACUUCAUCAACUGGGACCUGCAAAUGUACUAUGCUGAGAAGGACACACCCGCAAAAGCUAGAACCACCACACUCAAUGAACAGCUCGGGCAGAUCCAUUAUAUCUUCUCUGAUAAGACGGGGACACUCACACAAAAUAUCAUGACCUUUAAAAAGUGCUGUAUCAACGGGCAGAUAUAUGGGGACCAUCGGGAUGCCUCUCAACACAACCACAACAAAAUAGAGCAAGUUGAUUUUAGCUGGAAUACAUAUGCUGAUGGGAAGCUUGCAUUUUAUGACCACUAUCUUAUUGAGCAAAUCCAGUCAGGGAAAGAGCCAGAAGUACGACAGUUCUUCUUCUUGCUCGCAGUUUGCCACACAGUCAUGGUGGAUAGGACUGAUGGUCAGCUCAACUACCAGGCAGCCUCUCCCGAUGAAGGUGCCCUGGUAAACGCUGCCAGGAACUUUGGCUUUGCCUUCCUCGCCAGGACCCAGAACACCAUCACCAUCAGUGAACUGGGCACUGAAAGGACUUACAAUGUUCUUGCCAUUUUGGACUUCAACAGUGACCGGAAGCGAAUGUCUAUCAUUGUAAGAACCCCAGAAGGCAAUAUCAAGCUUUACUGUAAAGGUGCUGACACUGUUAUUUAUGAACGGUUACAUCGAAUGAAUCCUACUAAGCAAGAAACACAGGAUGCCCUGGAUAUCUUUGCAAAUGAAACUCUUAGAACCCUAUGCCUUUGCUACAAGGAAAUUGAAGAAAAAGAAUUUACAGAAUGGAAUAAAAAGUUUAUGGCUGCCAGUGUGGCCUCCACCAACCGGGACGAAGCUCUGGAUAAAGUAUAUGAGGAGAUUGAAAAAGACUUAAUUCUCCUGGGAGCUACAGCUAUUGAAGACAAGCUACAGGAUGGAGUUCCAGAAACCAUUUCAAAACUUGCAAAAGCUGACAUUAAGAUCUGGGUGCUUACUGGAGACAAAAAGGAAACUGCUGAAAAUAUAGGAUUUGCUUGUGAACUUCUGACUGAAGACACCACCAUCUGCUAUGGGGAGGAUAUUAAUUCUCUUCUUCAUGCAAGGAUGGAAAACCAGAGGAAUAGAGGUGGCGUCUACGCAAAGUUUGCACCUCCUGUGCAGGAAUCUUUUUUUCCACCCGGUGGAAACCGUGCCUUAAUCAUCACUGGUUCUUGGUUGAAUGAAAUUCUUCUCGAGAAAAAGACCAAGAGAAAUAAGAUUCUGAAGCUGAAGUUCCCAAGAACAGAAGAAGAAAGACGGAUGCGGACCCAAAGUAAAAGGAGGCUAGAAGCUAAGAAAGAGCAGCGGCAGAAAAACUUUGUGGACCUGGCCUGCGAGUGCAGCGCAGUCAUCUGCUGCCGCGUCACCCCCAAGCAGAAGGCCAUGGUGGUGGACCUGGUGAAGAGGUACAAGAAAGCCAUCACGCUGGCCAUCGGAGAUGGGGCCAAUGACGUGAACAUGAUCAAAACUGCCCACAUUGGCGUUGGAAUAAGUGGACAAGAAGGAAUGCAAGCUGUCAUGUCGAGUGACUAUUCCUUUGCUCAGUUCCGAUAUCUGCAGAGGCUACUGCUGGUGCAUGGCCGAUGGUCUUACAUAAGGAUGUGCAAGUUCCUACGAUACUUCUUUUACAAAAACUUUGCCUUUACUUUGGUUCAUUUCUGGUACUCCUUCUUCAAUGGCUACUCUGCGCAGACUGCAUACGAGGAUUGGUUCAUCACCCUCUACAACGUGCUGUACACCAGCCUGCCCGUGCUCCUCAUGGGGCUGCUCGACCAGGAUGUGAGUGACAAACUGAGCCUCCGAUUCCCUGGGUUAUACAUAGUGGGACAAAGAGACUUACUAUUCAACUAUAAGAGAUUCUUUGUAAGCUUGUUGCAUGGGGUCCUAACAUCGAUGAUCCUCUUCUUCAUACCUCUUGGAGCUUAUCUGCAAACCGUAGGGCAGGAUGGAGAGGCACCUUCCGACUACCAGUCUUUUGCCGUCACCAUUGCCUCUGCUCUUGUAAUAACAGUCAAUUUCCAGAUUGGCUUGGAUACUUCUUAUUGGACUUUUGUGAAUGCUUUUUCAAUUUUUGGAAGCAUUGCACUUUAUUUUGGCAUCAUGUUUGACUUUCAUAGUGCUGGAAUACAUGUUCUCUUUCCAUCUGCAUUUCAAUUUACAGGCACAGCUUCAAACGCUCUGAGACAGCCAUACAUUUGGUUAACUAUCAUCCUGGCUGUUGCUGUGUGCUUACUACCCGUCGUUGCCAUUCGAUUCCUGUCAAUGACCAUCUGGCCAUCAGAAAGUGAUAAGAUCCAGAAGCAUCGCAAGCGGUUGAAGGCGGAGGAGCAGUGGCAGCGACGGCAGCAGGUGUUCCGCCGGGGCGUGUCAACGCGGCGCUCGGCCUACGCCUUCUCGCACCAGCGGGGCUACGCGGACCUCAUCUCCUCCGGGCGCAGCAUCCGCAAGAAGCGCUCGCCGCUUGAUGCCAUCGUGGCGGAUGGCACCGCGGAGUACAGGCGCACCGGGGACAGCUGAUCCCUUACCCCCAGGCUGGGAUGCGGCCACAAAGCACGUCUAUUUUUUUAUGAAAGACUCUCAGGACUUUGUGUGUGUGUGUGAAUUGCAUUCAUCACAAAGAUAUUGAAGACAAUAAAUAAUCUUUAUAACAAACUCCUUGGGUUGGACUAUUAAACAAUAGCAGAGCCAAGAAAUAGGACUUUUAAAAGUCCUAUUAUUCGGCCGGGCGUGGUGGCUCAGGUCUGUAAUCCCAGCACUUUAGGAGGCUGAGGAGGGGAGAUCACCUGAGGCCAGGAGUUCGAGACCAGCCCAGCCAACAUGGUGAAACCCUGUCUCUACCAUAAAUUAAAAAUUAGCCGGGCUUGGUGGUGGGCACCCGUAAUCCCACCUAUUUGAGAAGCUGAAGCAGAAGAAUCGCUUGAACCUGGGAGAUGGAGGUUACAGUGAGCCGAGAUUGCGCCACUGCACUCCAGCCUGGGUGACAGAGCAAGACUCUGUCUUAAGAAAAAUUUAAAAAUAGGCCGGGCAUGGUGGCUCAUGCCUGUCAUCCUAGCACUUUGGGAGGCCAAGGCAGGUGGAUCACUUGAGGUCAGGAGACCAGCCCGGCCAACAUGGUGAAACCCCAUCUCUACUAAAAAUACAAAAAUUAGCUGGAAAUCGCUUGAACCUGGGAGGUGGAGGUUCCAGUGAGCCGAGAUCGUGGCACUGCACUCCAACCUGAGCAACAGAGUGAGACACCAGCUCAAAAAAAAUUUUUUAAUAAUAAUAAAAGUCCUAUUAUUCAACUGGUUAUGUACAUUAUGGUUGAAAGGGAACGUUUUAAUCCAGUCUCAAUCCAGGGCAAUAGAAUUACAAAGCAUGUUGUAUUUCAGUUCAAAUGGUAUUGUAUUAUAAAAUUACAGUUACAUUUUCCUUUCGGUGAUCUUCAGCAUAAUUUCCCAGAGGCCCCUUUUUCCUCCCUAUAGGCCAUCUUAUUAACAGAUUUUAAAAUUUAUAGUAAUGACAAAUGACUUAUCAGUGUUCAUCAUCUGAAAGCUAAGUGGUUCGUUCAAUCACUUUUUCAAAGUUGAUAGUAGAUUGCAUGGUUUCAUGUUUCCUCAUAUUGGUUUAUUAAUUCUAUUUAAUCAAGGAAAAUAACUUCAGAUUCCAUAAAGUUUCAGUUUAUUUUUAGUUUACUACUAGGUGAGAUAGCACAUUACAUACUUUUACUAUCAAAUAUUAUUUUAGCAGCUUCCCAUAGUACCAAAUGAUUUGAUUCCCUACUCUCAUUUUUUAAAGCAUAUAAAUAUUUAUGGGCUUAAAAAGGGGGUUUUUAAAAACUGAGGAUAUCAGUAAUAAAUUGCAGAAUAUUUUGCAAAGCUUUCUUUUGGAAAGCAAACUUUUGUGCCUGCCUAUAUGCAAAGUAUUUUAUCAGGGACUUGAACAAAGACCUCACUCUUUUUCACUUGUCUUAUGUCGAGAGAAAAGGUUAUUGGCAGCCACAUUCCUAAGACUGGGGAAUGGUGUGUCCUUUUAAAUUUGAAGAUAACUUUAGGUAAUUAUGGAAACUCCUCAAAGAGGAGAAAGUAAUUUUUUUCCAGACAUUUUUCUCAUUCUGUGUCUUUCACACACUAGUUUCCAUAGUUCGAGAAUUCUGUUUUUUACCAUUGGGCUGUGAAUGUUCACAAUAUCAGUCCUGUUGAAUUCCUAUGAGGUAAUCACAAUGUGUAUAUGUUCAUUUUCUAGGUAUGAUAAAAGAAUGUAUGGCUUUUUAUUCUGUGGAAGUAAAAUCCUGAACGUUUACAACUUUUCCUUAACUUGUAAAUAAAAAAUUGUAAGUUUUUUCUUUUUUUACAGAAAACUUAGCUUGUGUAAUUCUGUUAGUUUCAGAUUUCUCUCCUGUUUUUGCAAAUUGUGGGAAAGAUUGACAAUGCAAAUGUGUCAAAGACAUACUGUUGGGUGCAAUAUUAACAAUUUUAAAUGCAAAUUUCUUUGGAUAAAUUAUUUCUAUAUUCUGUAAAUCUGAGAUUUAAUGUAUAUUUUGUUUAAAAAAAUGAUUUAGUAAAAUCUUUGAAAAGUAUGAUCUUCUAAAGUAUUUAAA